CUCCGGCGGCUGCAGAUUGACGGGACGAGAUGGUCCUGGCAGGGCUCAUCAGGAAACUCGGUCAUCAGCUGGCCGAGAUCAGGGAGCGCGCUCUCAAGAGUAUUCUCUGCAAGAUUGAGCACAACUUAAUCUGCUACGCUGAUCUCAUUCAGGAGAGGCAACUUUUUCUUCAUUUGCUGGAAUGGUUCAAUUUCCCGUCCGUUCCGAUGAAGGAAGAGGUUCUGAACCUGUUAAGCAGAUUGGUUAAGUAUCCCCCAGCAGUCCAACAUUUGGUUGACGUUGGUGCAGUAGAGUUCUUAUCUAAGCUUCGGUCUAAUGUGGAGCCAAAUCUGCAGGCUGAAAUUGAUGGCAUUCUGGAUGGACUUUUUCUUCUUCCUUCGGAAGUUCCUGCACUAUCUUCUGCCUCAUACCAAACCAAUCAAACUGAAUUGUCAAAAAACCCUGAAAUCUUAACAGGAUAUUUUCCCCAAGACAAAAGUAAUUUCCAGCAGAUGGAAGUGCCGCCACGACCAGUGGUAAAUCAGACUGUGAAGUGCUUGAAGUUUUCUACAUUUCCUUGGCUACCCCUGACCACCACAGACAGACAUGUCCUCUCCUCUAAUGAAAGCUCUUUAAGAAGUAGUAACCACACUUUAAUCUGGAACACCUGUGAACUAUUGAAGGAUGUUAUCAUGCAAGAUUUUCCUGCUGAGAUUUUCCUUCAAAGGCCAAAAAUUGUUCAGAGCCUUUUAUCUCUGUUGAAACUGGCCUUUGGAGAUGGAAAGCAUCGCCUGGCAUUACAGUCGGUGUCCUGCCUGCAGCAGCUGUGCAUGUAUUUAAGAAACAGACUUAACUUUCACCGAGAUCCAGGUUUUUUCUCCAAUAAACACGACACAGUUUCCCAAAAUUCUUCUUUGUCUUAUUGUCAUGAAGCAAGAGGUACUCAUCAUUCCCAGAAUCCUUCCCCAGGAAGCAGCAGCCCUCGGCCUUCUGUGGUUGGGCGCACAGGCCAGCGACCCAGAGGAGAUGGCCAGGACUGGGAUGCAGCGUCCUCUAGUGGAAGUAGUAGUCAUGCUCAUGUAAACUCCAGGAUAUCCGUUCAUUCACCUUUGGAUAUGGGACACAUAGAUCUGCCAGAGCUGGAAACUGAAGACACAUUGGAACUACAAUUCCAGCAGCUCAGUCUUCCCCAGUUUUGUGUCUCCAUUCUGGAAUCAGCUGUUCCUCUCUUAAGAACAGGUAGCAGACAAGUGAUAAUAAGAGUUCUGGAAUUGCUUACAGAGGAUAUGACACUUAUUGGUGAAGCAAUUUCAACAGAUAUCUGGGAUGACAGCAGCCUUUUUGGUAUAGAUAUGAAGGAGAAACUACUCCUGGUGUUGGGAGCCCUUGGAGAAACCAUGUGCUACCAUAAAAGUAGUAUCAGUUUGGAGCAGCCAGAGGUGAUGCUUGUGCACCACAGAAUGGCCUUUAUCAGCAUUUCCCUGUUUGCAGUUCGACUGCUACAAACGCUUCUCCCUGUUGAAAAGGCAAGCGAGUUUUUAUCAGAGCCUAUGUCAACAGCAUUAUUUCUCCUUUCUUUGGACAUGCCUAUUUCUUUGGAAUAUCCAAAUAUUCAUGAAGCUGUUGUGGCCUAUUUGGAACAGCUGAAUUCUGAAAACUACAGUAUUUAUAAACGAACUGCAGAGGCCGUUUAUUCAAUUGAAUGCACCUGUAACUUCCUGUCUGAUAUUGGGAAAGAGGGAGAGAAGAAUCUCUUAGAAUUAGUGGAGCUGGCAGACCAAGCCUUGCGUAGCUUUUCCUAUCAUCAGCAUUUCCCGCUAAUAAAGGAAAUCAUCAGCAUUUGUUCAAAGAUCUGGAAAUCUGCUCAGGCCAGUCCAUUACUACAAGGAGAAAGUCAGAAGGUGCUUCUCCAUAUGUUGUCUCACCCAUUGCCACGAGUGAAAGCUGAAACUUACCACUGCUGUCUGGAAAUCACGAAGGAAUGUUUAGGUGUCCAUAAUGUCACUAAACCCGUGUCUUCACUUUGCAAUGGAAUUCAUUUUCUACUUCAUCCAAAAGUUCUGUAUGAAAUCUCUGUAUUUGGCAUUCAAGAGCCCGAAAGUGAGCAGGUGAACACUGCUGCCAAGGCCAUUCUGUUAUACCUGCUUCAGGGACGAUUGAUGAUGACAGCAUUGACCUGGAACAAGUUUAUUGAAUCUCUCUGUCCUGUCAUCCCAAUACUACAGGGCUAUGCCGACACAGAAGAUCCUCUGGGUAACUGCAUUCUCCUUCUAAGCAAAGCAAGUUCUGACACAGAAGAGAUGCUUCCGUGUACUACCCGAUUAAAGUCCAUGCUGCGACUUUUGCUAGUGAAAAAGCCAUCGGUCCGUUCGCUAGCAUUAAAGCUUUUAGCAUUCCAUCUUACCAGUGAAGAAGGGGCUGAUACAAAGCGUCCUCUAAUAGACGCCAGAGUUCUCUCCAGAGUUACUGAUUUAUUCAUUGGGAAGAAACCUAUUGAACUCAGACUGGAUGACAGAAGAGAGCUGGUUAUUAAGUUGGAGACUGUUGAAAAGGUAUAUGAAAUCUUCACCUCAGAUGAUGUUGAUCUCGUUUUGAGAAAGUCAGCUGCUGAACAGUUAGCUGUGAUUAUGCAAGAUAUUAAAAUGCAUGCUGUGGUGAAAAAGUUAUGCUUAAUUGACAAAAUAAUUGAGUAUUUAAAUGAAUGUGUGAGUCAAGAUGGCAAGGUUGUAGAAUGUUUGGUACAACCAUGCCUCACACUCUUGAGGAAGGUUUUAUGUGGUGAUCCAGUCAUGCGUGUUUCGCUCUCGCAACAGUCUUCUCUUUUGACCGUGUUAUUCAGAGUUUCCUUAAUAUUUCAUGAAGAUUGUAGUGUCGUGACUGAAGUUGGAGCACUAUUUUGUCUUCUAUUAUUUGAUGAAGUAUCGAGAAUGGAUAUGUGGUCUGUUAAUCCUUCCAAUAAACCUUCUUUGCCAUCGGUCUUCAGUUUGCCUGUUUCCGUUUUUAGAAGGUACCAUCUACCUGUUCAUGUAAUUGGACACCAUGCUGUGAGUCCUUACUCCAUAGUUUUGCCCUUAUCUGCUGAUUGUUUGGCCUUGAAGCCGGUGUCAGAUAUGCUGAGAAUAGCUUGGAACCUGUCAUGGUAUCAUGGGAGUGAUAAUCUGUUGAAGCAAAUGAACUCUGAAACUAAAACGCAAGAAAUUUUAGAUGCAUUGAAGUUAUCUACAGAGGACAUCCUCACUCUGAAGAUAACACACAUGGCUAGUGGGCUGCAGGACUGCCUCCAUUCCAUUGUUCAGGCUGCAACCCACAGGGAAGUUAGGGCUGCUGUCACCAGGAUGAGUUUUUAUCUUCUGAAUGACAGAUUGUCUUUAAAGGGUUGCCCUGGUCCAUGUGGGGUUACCUUGAAGUCCUUGGCUUGGCACACCGCACUAAACAGGUUUUUACAGGUGCUUCCUGCUUGCACUGAAGAUGAGAAACUGCUAAUAGAUAUCAUACAUUUUUUAAAUAAAUUAAUAAAGGAACAAAGAAAAAAUUCUUCACUAGAACUUCUAAACUGGAUUCUCGAAUUACUUCUUAGACAUAGUGCAAACCCACUGUUAGACCUCUUGGUUCUGACAGAGUCACAGGCACGAGAAGAAACAGAUGAUAUCCGGACUGCUGUCAGGCAACAACUUCAGAAAGAACUGAUUGCUCUUUUUGAUACCUUGCUGCUCAAUUUCAUGGAAGUUACUGACAGGAAAUGCUCGGAACUUCUUUACGUUUUUCAAACGCAGCUGGCUCUGAAACUGCUCCAGUGUCUGAAAGUGACGGAUGCGCCUCAUUUCUAUGGCCUGCCGUCCCUUGAGCGGACCUUACGAGGGAUGGCUAACCUCACUGCGUUUCCGGGAUGGAGCUCACACUCUCCUCUCACAAAGCCUCUAGAUAUCUGUGUGAAGUACUUGUCAGGUCUCCUUGAGGUCAUUACUUCUUUUUAUGUGGAGCGUGGAGGAAAUGCUAUGUCCUUCAUGGGAAAAGGUGUUACAAAGAGCACAAUUCUUUGCUUGCUUCACUUAUCCCAUGAGAUGAUGGCCCAGGCUGGGAGCUUGGAGUGGAUGUCACUUUGGUUCUUGCCUUUGGGUAGUCAUAGUGAAGAACAUAUUCCUACUCAACAAGGAUUGGCUUGGUUGAUUCCAUUAUGGGUUGAUCGGGACCCAGAGGUGAGAUUCACUUCACUGGGAUUAGGAUCAGCACUGACCACCCUUGAAACGGGCUGUGUGGCCUUAGCAAACAGUUGUCAGAACAUUUCCGGUGGGCUCUGGGGAACUGUGGUGAACAUUCUUCUGGACCAGUCAGAAUGUAGUAUGGUGCGCCGGGAGGCGGCAUUUAUUCUUCAGAAUCUCCUUGUAAUUCCAAUGCCUACAGAAAUUAUAAAGGAUUAUACUUGGCAGGGUCCCUGUGUUCAUGAUGAGGACUCUGGCCUAUCGCUCAUUGGAAAACCUGCCCUUCAGGCUCUUUUAUAUCACUGCCAUUUUUAUGAACAUUUGAAUCAGAUGGUAAAGCAUUGUUACCUAGGACGGUGUAUGUUUGAUUUGAAUUUUUCUGCUUUUGAUAGAAAUUCAGAAAGCAAUGAUUUAAAUGGUUUAGAUGACUCAUUCAAGUUUUGGAGGGCUCCAUCUAGGACAAGUCAGGAUCGAGAUCCAAGUUCUCUCUCCACCUCAGAAACAACGGUGGCACCUUCAUUGGGGAGUACUGAAUUUCAGCCACUUGUGCAGUCAACAACACUUCUACCUGAAGCCUCCCAUGACCAGUUUGUGGCUCAAGGUCACCAGGAAAGUACAUCACCACGGCCACCUCAUGAUUCAUCUCUUUCUGCUCCCCUGCCCAAACUGUGUGUUUUUGUUACUCCAUCUCUUCUUUCAGCAAUGUGCAGCCUCUUGGACAACCUCUUGACGAUUGCUCCCAGAGACACUGCAAAGGCUUUUCGACAAGCUCAUCUCAUAGAACUUCUCUGUAGCAUUGCAGAUGCUACCCUCAUACAGACAUGUGUCCAGGAACUCAGAGCCCUGCUGCCUUCAUCACCUCCAGCUGAACACACUCAGGCUCAGGUUUCCUUUCUCCUGGAAUACCUAUCCUCUUUGUCCAGGCUUCUGCAGUCAUGUUUAUUGGUGGAGCCUGACCUUGUGAUUCAGGAUGAGCUUGUGAAACCUCUUAUCACCAAUAUCAUUGGAAUUCUCACCAUAUGUACCAAAGAUGUAUUAGAUAAAGAGUUAAUAUCAGCUUUUUAUCACACAUGGACACAUUUAUUUAAUCUUCUGGCCAUGCUCCUGAGGAAAGCUGGUGCCAUCACACUCCCGUUUGUUACCGUGGCCCUGGCCAAGCACUGGACAGCGGCGAUUGAUAUGUUCUGCACAUGUGCAGGCUUGUCUGCCACGUGUCCUGCCCUGUAUACUGCCAGCUUGCAAUUCCUUUCUGUUCUCUUGACCGAAGAAGCAAAAGGGCAUCUCCAGGCUAAGAGCAAAACACAUUUAUGCUGUAGUCCAACAGUGGCUUCACUUCUUGAUGACUCUCAGGAAAAUCAGAAAUCUCUAGAACAACUUAGUGAUGUAAUCCUUCAGUGCUAUGAAGGGAAAUCCUCCAAAGAUAUCCUGAAAAGAGUAGCUGCAAAUGCAUUGAUGUCACUGCUGGCUGUCAGUAGAAGAGCACAGAAACAUGCUUUGAAAGCCAAUCUUAUAGACAAUUGCAUGGAGCAGAUGAAACACAUAAAUGCACAACUGAACCUAGAUUCUCUGAGGCCUGGGAAAGCAGCAUUGAAAAAAAAGGAGGAUGGUGUUAUUAAAGAGUUAAGCAUUGCCAUGCAGCUCCUAAGAAACUGUCUUUAUCAAAAUGAGGAAUGUAAAGAAGCAGCUCUUGAAGCUCACCUUGUCCCUGUCUUGCACUCUCUCUGGCCUUGGAUUUUGAUGGAUGAUUCAUUGAUGCAAAUUUCUCUGCAGCUCCUUUGUGUCUAUACUGCAAAUUUUCCAAAUGGUUGCAGUUCUCUUUGUUGGUCAAGUUGUGGACAACACCCUGUUCAAGCUACACAUAGAGGAGCCGUGAGCAACUCUCUGAUGCUGUGUAUCCUAAAGUUGGCUUCCCAGAUGCCACUGGAGAACACCACGGUUCAGCAGAUGGUUUUUAUGCUUCUUUCAAACCUGGCCUUGUCGCAUGACUGUAAAGGAGUAAUUCAGAAGGCCAAGAUAAAUUGCAGAAGUUGAGAGCAUUUAUAAGAAUUGAGUCUCCUUUUCCUCUACUGUUUCUUCUCCCUGAACUCCUCAGAAGAUACUUUGUUAUCACCACAUAAAUAGAAAGUUCGGUCUUUCUAAGGAAAUGGAAAGAUCAAUCUUACCAAGGAAAGAUGUUUUCAGUGGCACGUUGGAGCCAGCCUCCUACUGACUCAUGAGUGUCAUCUUAAAUUUGCAGGAAUUUUAUAAAAAUUCCAGUUGAUGUUACAUUGUUAUUUUGAAAUCAGCCACAGUGGGCAUAUCACACCACGUAAUUCAGCGAACUGUACAAAUCUUGGAUCUUUUCUACCCUCACCACAAUCAGUUGUUUAUUUACCAGCACAUGGCUGGAUAUUUUCUUCAUGUAUAUGUUCAUGUAUGUCAUAUAUGUAUAUAUAUUUGAAUAUAUUUUCUUCAUAUAUGUAUUCAUAUACAUGCAUCACUUCCAAAAUGAGACAUUCUCUUGAACUGGAUAUAUGUGAUUAGCAUCCAUAAGAAUGAGAGAUUCUGCAUAUGUGAGAGCAGAGCGGGGGCAGUGCUUUCCACCACUUCCUUAUAGAGCAUGUUGGUGGGAAGCUAAGUGGGAGCACCCAGAAGGAAUGUAAGUGCCAAUCUCGAGUCUGGUCUGUGACUUUGAGCUGGAGACCUAUUCUCUUUCAGCUUCAUUUGGGUUUAACAAAAUAAUCUCUAAGAUAUGUUCAACUCUUAAUCUGUUAUUCUGGUGCUAUACUUAAGAAUAUUUUGAUGAAGUGUGAUCAGACUCUCUUUCCAGGGACGGAUUAAUCAAGUCUUUUUCCUCUGCUCUAAUUAGGAAAUGCCUGAGACUUCCUCUGCUGCAUUAAGUAAUAAUGAGCCCAGACACUUAACACUUCUACUUCUUCAUUACUCAUCUGUAGGACAUAGAAAAUGCAGCAGGUGGUAUUGUACAACUCAGGCUCCGAAAUAUCCUGCUUGUUUGUUUUUUUUUCUACCAUGGUAUACAUCUCUACAUAUUCUACCUGGUGUAGGAAAUUGUCUGAAAACAUCUUUAGAAGCAGCAAAAAAAAAAAAAAAAAAAAAAAAAAGGAGUGCCCACAGCACAUUUAUAUUUGAGAGCACUGACAUCUGCUUUAUCACCCUUGUCAGUCCCAAAUCCAGCAAGGGUUGAAUCUAAAAACUGUCAGUUUGGCUGACAGUAGGUGUGAGUGACAGCACAUGCAGCUGAAAGUGGGCAUGUAAUUUUACAGUUUACUUAUUGUGUGGGUAAUGUUGAUAAUAUUUCUGUAGCUCAUUUCAUUCUUAACACUCAGAGUCCUUUUGUAUAAAAACGUUAAGUUUAUUUUAUAGAUUAAAGCCAACAUCUUGAUUUUGGUCUAGGAAAACCUAAGAGAUAAACUGGAGUAGAUUUAAACAGAGAGAGAGAAGAGUUAUUCUGUGCAAUCAUAAAAGUUAAGUGAUUGCAUUUCAUUUCUAAAAUGUCCACCUAACUGUGGUUUCCAUGCUGCCAUGGGCUGCAGCUUGAUGCAGCACUUUUAUACUUUGCAUAUAGAUUAGUCUAAGCAAUAAUUUAUUAUCUUUCUUAUAGUGAAGGGUUUGGUGGGGUUUUUUGGAAGGGGCUUUAUUUGGAGGUUGAAAAGACUCUUACAGUUCAAAUAAUAGAGCUUUCUCAUCUGUAAGCAUAAUAGAAUGACGUGUAGCCAUCAGAAAUUCUUACUUGUAAUGAUAAGUACCUGGGAUAAAGUGAAUGUAAGAUGUAUCUAUAGAUUUGAUAAAAACAACAACAACACCUGUAGCUAUAAUGAUUCAAAAUACCCUCACUACUUCCAGAGUUGUUAACUAGUAUUCAAGACUGAUUUGGAUUUUUGCCUUUUUUCCUUCCAUAGGGUAGCUUUUAAUAGCAAAAUCACCAGAAGGCAGAGAGAAGAGAAAACUCAAGAGCCCUGAAAUAAUCUCCAAACUUAAUUACCAAUUCUAAAUAAUUAAGAGUUAACUAUAGUAUACUUCAUCCAUCAUGAGGAAAUAAUUAGCAGGAAUUAAAACUUGAGCACUAUUUUGUUCUUCUUACCUUUUUCACUUAUGCUUGGAAAUAAUAUAGAUGGAAUAUUCAGAAGCUAUUAGAAAGGAGAAAUUAAUGUAGAGGGAGAGUAUAUCAGAAUGUUAGUUAAUUGGUCACCAAGGGACUAGGAAAAUAAUGAAAAAGAUGAGAAGAAAAUAAUAUUCUCUCUAUUUAU